AAGCGCACCGCCCAGGCAGCAGCCGGCCGCCGGGGUCUGCGCGGCGCGGAGCUGCCCAGCCCGCUCCGGGAACUCAGCCCCCGCCCCGCGCCGGGCCCGCCCCGCUUCCCACGCCCGUCCGGCCGAGCCCGCGCCGGAGCCACCUGGAGCCGCCUGGAGCCGCCGCCGCCGCCGCAGGUUGAUGCGCGGCGCCCUCCCGGGACGCGCGGAGGAGCCAUCUUGAAACCAACUUCGCAAACUUUCGCAAAGUGCUCUCGAAGUGGAAGCUGCGGGGGAGGCCGGGCGCGUGGUCCCCACAGUCCCCGCCAGGGCCCCCGGGGAGGCGGGACGCGGACCGCCCCGAGGGCCGGGCGCCCGGGAGCCGCUCCCCGGCCUCGCCGGGUGGAUGCGGAGGCGCGCCGGGUGCAUGGAUUGUGUUCGGGCGCCCGGCUCGGGCUCGGGCUCCGGGCCAUGGCGCCGCCGCCGCCGCCCGUGCUGCCCGUGCUGCUGCUCCUGGCCGCCGCCGCCGCCCUGCCGGCGAUGGGGCUGCGAGCGGCCGCCUGGGAGCCGCGCGUACCCGGCGGGACCCGCGCCUUCGCCCUCCGGCCCGGCUGUACCUACGCGGUGGGCGCCGCUUGCACGCCCCGGGCGCCGCGGGAGCUGCUGGACGUGGGCCGCGAUGGGCGGCUGGCAGGACGUCGGCGCGUCUCGGGCGCGGGGCGCCCGCUGCCGCUGCAAGUCCGCUUGGUGGCCCGCAGUGCCCCGACGGCGCUGAGCCGCCGCCUGCGGGCGCGCACGCACCUUCCCGGCUGCGGAGCCCGUGCCCGGCUCUGCGGAACCGGUGCCCGGCUCUGCGGGGCGCUCUGCUUCCCCGUCCCCGGCGGCUGCGCGGCCGCGCAGCAUUCGGCGCUCGCAGCUCCGACCACCUUACCCGCCUGCCGCUGCCCGCCGCGCCCCAGGCCCCGCUGUCCCGGCCGUCCCAUCUGCCUGCCGCCGGGCGGCUCGGUCCGCCUGCGUCUGCUGUGCGCCCUGCGGCGCGCGGCUGGCGCCGUCCGGGUGGGACUGGCGCUGGAGGCCGCCACCGCGGGGACGCCCUCCGCGUCGCCAUCCCCAUCGCCGCCCCUGCCGCCGAACUUGCCCGAAGCCCGGGCGGGGCCGGCGCGACGGGCCCGGCGGGGCACGAGCGGCAGAGGGAGCCUGAAGUUUCCGAUGCCCAACUACCAGGUGGCGUUGUUUGAGAACGAACCGGCGGGCACCCUCAUCCUCCAGCUGCACGCGCACUACACCAUCGAGGGCGAGGAGGAGCGCGUGAGCUAUUACAUGGAGGGGCUGUUCGACGAGCGCUCCCGGGGCUACUUCCGAAUCGACUCUGCCACGGGCGCCGUGAGCACGGACAGCGUACUGGACCGCGAGACCAAGGAGACGCACGUCCUCAGGGUGAAAGCCGUGGACUACAGUACGCCGCCGCGCUCGGCCACCACCUACAUCACUGUCUUGGUCAAAGACACCAACGACCACAGCCCGGUCUUCGAGCAGUCGGAGUACCGCGAGCGCGUGCGGGAGAACCUGGAGGUGGGCUACGAGGUGCUGACCAUCCGCGCCAGCGACCGCGACUCGCCCAUCAACGCCAACUUGCGUUACCGCGUGUUGGGGGGCGCGUGGGACGUCUUCCAGCUCAACGAGAGCUCUGGCGUGGUGAGCACACGGGCGGUGCUGGACCGGGAGGAGGCGGCCGAGUACCAGCUCCUGGUGGAGGCCAACGACCAGGGGCGCAAUCCGGGCCCGCUCAGUGCCACGGCCACCGUGUACAUCGAGGUGGAGGACGAGAACGACAACUACCCCCAGUUCAGCGAGCAGAACUACGUGGUCCAGGUGCCCGAGGACGUGGGGCUCAACACGGCUGUGCUGCGAGUGCAGGCCACGGACCGGGACCAGGGCCAGAACGCGGCCAUUCACUACAGCAUCCUCAGCGGGAACGUGGCCGGCCAGUUCUACCUGCACUCGCUGAGCGGGAUCCUGGAUGUGAUCAACCCCUUGGAUUUCGAGGAUGUCCAGAAAUACUCGCUGAGCAUUAAGGCCCAGGAUGGGGGCCGGCCCCCGCUCAUCAAUUCUUCAGGGGUGGUGUCUGUGCAGGUGCUGGAUGUCAACGACAACGAGCCUAUCUUUGUGAGCAGCCCCUUCCAGGCCACGGUGCUGGAGAAUGUGCCCCUGGGCUACCCCGUGGUGCACAUUCAGGCGGUGGACGCGGACUCUGGAGAGAACGCCCGGCUGCACUAUCGCCUGGUGGACACGGCCUCCACCUUUCUGGGGGGCGGCAGCGCUGGGCCUAAGAAUCCUGCCCCCACCCCUGACUUCCCCUUCCAGAUCCACAACAGCUCCGGUUGGAUCACAGUGUGUGCCGAGCUGGACCGCGAGGAGGUGGAGCACUACAGCUUCGGGGUGGAGGCGGUGGACCACGGCUCGCCCCCCAUGAGCUCCUCCACCAGCGUGUCCAUCACGGUGCUGGACGUGAAUGACAACGACCCGGUGUUCACGCAGCCCACCUACGAGCUUCGUCUGAAUGAGGAUGCGGCCGUGGGGAGCAGCGUGCUGACCCUGCAGGCCCGCGACCGUGACGCCAACAGUGUGAUUACCUACCAGCUCACAGGCGGCAACACCCGGAACCGCUUUGCACUCAGCAGCCAGAGAGGGGGCGGCCUCAUCACCCUGGCGCUACCUCUGGACUACAAGCAGGAGCAGCAGUACGUGCUGGCGGUGACAGCAUCCGACGGCACACGGUCGCACACUGCGCAUGUCCUAAUCAACGUCACUGAUGCCAACACCCACAGGCCUGUCUUUCAGAGCUCCCAUUACACAGUGAGUGUCAGUGAGGACAGGCCUGUGGGCACCUCCAUUGCUACCCUCAGUGCCAACGAUGAGGACACAGGAGAGAAUGCCCGCAUCACCUACGUGAUUCAGGACCCCGUGCCGCAGUUCCGCAUUGACCCCGACAGUGGCACCAUGUACACCAUGAUGGAGCUGGACUAUGAGAACCAGGUCGCCUACACGCUGACCAUCAUGGCCCAGGACAACGGCAUCCCGCAGAAAUCAGACACCACCACCCUAGAGAUCCUCAUCCUCGAUGCCAAUGACAAUGCACCCCAGUUCCUGUGGGAUUUCUACCAGGGUUCCAUCUUUGAGGAUGCUCCACCCUCGACCAGCAUCCUCCAGGUCUCUGCCACGGACCGGGACUCAGGUCCCAAUGGGCGUCUGCUGUACACCUUCCAGGGUGGGGACGACGGCGAUGGGGACUUCUACAUCGAGCCCACGUCCGGUGUGAUUCGCACCCAGCGCCGGCUGGACCGGGAGAAUGUGGCCGUGUACAACCUUUGGGCUCUGGCUGUGGAUCGGGGCAGUCCCACUCCCCUUAGCGCCUCGGUAGAAAUCCAGGUGACCAUCUUGGACAUUAAUGACAAUGCCCCCAUGUUUGAGAAGGACGAACUGGAGCUGUUUGUUGAGGAGAACAACCCAGUGGGGUCGGUGGUGGCAAAGAUUCGUGCUAACGACCCUGAUGAAGGCCCUAAUGCCCAGAUCAUGUAUCAGAUUGUGGAAGGGGACAUGCGGCAUUUCUUCCAGCUGGACCUGCUCAACGGGGACCUGCGUGCCAUGGUGGAGCUGGACUUUGAGGUCCGGCGGGAGUAUGUGCUGGUGGUGCAGGCCACGUCGGCUCCGCUGGUGAGCCGAGCCACGGUGCACAUCCUUCUCGUGGACCAGAAUGACAACCCGCCUGUGCUGCCCGACUUCCAGAUCCUCUUCAACAACUAUGUCACCAACAAGUCCAACAGUUUCCCCACCGGCGUGAUCGGCUGCAUCCCGGCCCAUGACCCCGACGUGUCAGACAGCCUCAACUACACCUUCGUGCAGGGCAACGAGCUGCGCCUGUUGCUGCUGGACCCCGCCACGGGCGAACUGCAGCUCAGCCGCGACCUGGACAACAACCGGCCGCUGGAGGCGCUCAUGGAGGUGUCUGUGUCUGAUGGCAUCCACAGCGUCACGGCCUUCUGCACCCUGCGUGUCACCAUCAUCACGGACGACAUGCUGACCAACAGCAUCACUGUCCGCCUGGAGAACAUGUCCCAGGAGAAGUUCCUGUCCCCGCUGCUGGCCCUCUUCGUGGAGGGGGUGGCCGCCGUGCUGUCCACCACCAAGGACGACGUCUUCGUCUUCAACGUCCAGAACGACACCGACGUCAGCUCCAACAUCCUGAACGUGACCUUCUCGGCGCUGCUGCCUGGCGGCGUCCGCGGCCAGUUCUUCCCGUCGGAGGACCUGCAGGAGCAGAUCUACCUGAAUCGGACGCUGCUGACCACCAUCUCCACGCAGCGCGUGCUGCCCUUCGACGACAACAUCUGCCUGCGCGAGCCCUGCGAGAACUACAUGAAGUGCGUGUCCGUUCUGCGAUUCGACAGCUCCGCGCCCUUCCUCAGCUCCACCACCGUGCUCUUCCGGCCCAUCCACCCCAUCAACGGCCUGCGCUGCCGCUGCCCGCCCGGCUUCACCGGCGACUACUGCGAGACGGAGAUCGACCUCUGCUACUCCGACCCGUGCGGCGCCAACGGCCGCUGCCGCAGCCGCGAGGGCGGCUACACCUGCGAGUGCUUCGAGGACUUCACUGGAGAGCACUGUGAGGUGGAUGCCCGCUCAGGCCGCUGUGCCAACGGGGUGUGCAAGAACGGGGGCACCUGCGUGAACCUGCUCAUCGGCGGCUUCCACUGCGUGUGUCCUCCUGGCGAGUAUGAGAGGCCCUACUGUGAGGUGACCACCAGGAGCUUCCCGCCCCAGUCCUUCGUCACCUUCCGGGGCCUGAGACAGCGCUUCCACUUCACCAUCUCCCUCACGUUUGCCACUCAGGAAAGGAACGGCUUGCUUCUCUACAACGGCCGCUUCAAUGAGAAGCACGACUUCAUCGCCCUGGAGAUCGUGGACGAGCAGGUGCAGCUCACCUUCUCUGCAGGCGAGACAACAACGACCGUGGCACCGAAGGUUCCCAGUGGUGUGAGUGACGGGCGGUGGCACUCUGUGCAGGUGCAGUACUACAACAAGCCCAAUAUUGGCCACCUGGGCCUGCCCCAUGGGCCGUCCGGGGAAAAGAUGGCCGUGGUGACAGUGGAUGAUUGUGACACAACCAUGGCUGUGCGCUUUGGAAAGGACAUCGGGAACUACAGCUGCGCUGCCCAGGGCACUCAGACCGGCUCCAAGAAGUCCCUGGAUCUGACCGGCCCUCUACUCCUGGGGGGUGUCCCCAACCUGCCAGAAGACUUCCCAGUGCACAACCGGCAGUUCGUGGGCUGCAUGCGGAACCUGUCAGUCGACGGCAAAAAUGUGGACAUGGCCGGAUUCAUCGCCAACAAUGGCACCCGGGAAGGCUGCGCUGCUCGGAGGAACUUCUGCGAUGGGAGGCGGUGUCAGAAUGGAGGCACCUGUGUCAACAGGUGGAAUAUGUAUCUGUGUGAGUGUCCACUCCGAUUCGGCGGGAAGAACUGUGAGCAAGCCAUGCCUCACCCCCAGCUCUUCAGCGGUGAGAGCGUCGUGUCCUGGAGUGACCUGAACAUCAUCAUCUCUGUGCCCUGGUACCUGGGGCUCAUGUUCCGGACCCGGAAGGAGGACAGCGUUCUGAUGGAGGCCACCAGUGGUGGGCCCACCAGCUUUCGCCUCCAGAUCCUGAACAACUACCUCCAGUUUGAGGUGUCCCACGGCCCCUCCGAUGUGGAGUCCGUGAUGCUGUCCGGGUUGCGGGUGACCGACGGGGAGUGGCACCACCUGCUGAUCGAGCUGAAGAAUGUUAAGGAGGACAGUGAGAUGAAGCACCUGGUCACCAUGACCUUGGACUAUGGGAUGGACCAGAACAAGGCAGAUAUCGGGGGCAUGCUUCCCGGGCUGACGGUAAGGAGCGUGGUGGUCGGAGGCGCCUCUGAAGACAAGGUCUCCGUGCGCCGUGGAUUCCGAGGCUGCAUGCAGGGAGUGAGGAUGGGGGGGACGCCCACCAACGUCGCCACCCUGAACAUGAACAACGCACUCAAGGUCAGGGUGAAGGACGGCUGUGAUGUGGACGACCCCUGUACCUCGAGCCCCUGUCCCCCCAAUAGCCGCUGCCACGACGCCUGGGAGGACUACAGCUGCGUCUGUGACAAAGGGUACCUUGGAAUAAACUGUGUGGAUGCCUGUCACCUGAACCCCUGCGAGAACAUGGGGGCCUGCGUGCGCUCCCCCGGCUCCCCGCAGGGCUACGUGUGCGAGUGUGGGCCCAGUCACUACGGGCCGUACUGUGAGAACAAACUCGACCUUCCGUGCCCCAGAGGCUGGUGGGGGAACCCCGUCUGUGGACCCUGCCACUGUGCCGUCAGCAAAGGCUUUGAUCCCGACUGUAAUAAGACCAACGGCCAGUGCCAAUGCAAGGAGAAUUACUACAAGCUCCUAGCCCAGGACACCUGUCUGCCCUGCGACUGCUUCCCCCAUGGCUCCCACAGCCGCACUUGCGACAUGGCCACCGGGCAGUGUGCCUGCAAGCCCGGCGUCAUCGGCCGCCAGUGCAACCGCUGCGACAACCCGUUUGCCGAGGUCACCACGCUCGGCUGUGAAGUGAUCUACAAUGGCUGUCCCAAAGCAUUUGAGGCCGGCAUCUGGUGGCCACAGACCAAGUUCGGGCAGCCGGCUGCGGUGCCAUGCCCUAAGGGAUCCGUUGGAAAUGCGGUCCGACACUGCAGCGGGGAGAAGGGCUGGCUGCCCCCAGAGCUCUUUAACUGUACCACCAUCUCCUUCGUGGACCUCAGGGCCAUGAAUGAGAAGCUGAGCCGCAAUGAGACGCAGGUGGACGGCGCCAGGGCCCUGCAGCUGGUGAGGGCGCUGCGCAGUGCUACACAGCACACGGGCACGCUCUUUGGCAAUGACGUGCGCACGGCCUACCAGCUGCUGGGCCACGUCCUUCAGCACGAGAGCUGGCAGCAGGGCUUCGACCUGGCAGCCACGCAGGACGCCGACUUUCACGAGGACGUCAUCCACUCGGGCAGCGCCCUCCUGGCCCCAGCCACCAGGGCGGCGUGGGAGCAGAUCCAGCGGAGCGAGGGCGGCACGGCACAGCUGCUCCGGCGCCUCGAGGGCUACUUCAGCAACGUGGCACGCAACGUGCGGCGGACGUACCUGCGGCCCUUCGUCAUCGUCACCGCCAACAUGAUUCUUGCUGUCGACAUCUUUGACAAGUUCAACUUUACGGGAGCCAGGGUCCCGCGAUUCGACACCAUCCAUGAAGAGUUCCCCAGGGAGCUGGAGUCCUCCGUCUCCUUCCCAGCCGACUUCUUCAGACCACCUGAAGAAAAAGAAGGCCCCCUGCUGAGGCCGGCUGGCCGGAGGACCACCCCGCAGACCACGCGCCCGGGGCCUGGCACCGAGAGGGAGGCCCCGAUCAGCAGGCGGAGGCGACACCCUGAUGACGCUGGCCAGUUCGCCGUCGCUCUGGUCAUCAUUUACCGCACCCUGGGGCAGCUCCUGCCCGAGCGCUACGACCCCGACCGUCGCAGCCUCCGGUUGCCUCACCGGCCCAUCAUUAAUACCCCGAUGGUGAGCACGCUGGUGUACAGCGAGGGGGCUCCGCUCCCGAGACCCCUGGAGAGGCCCGUCCUGGUGGAGUUCGCCCUGCUGGAGGUGGAGGAGCGAACCAAGCCUGUCUGCGUGUUCUGGAACCACUCCCUGGCCGUUGGUGGGACGGGAGGGUGGUCUGCCCGGGGCUGCGAGCUCCUGUCCAGGAACCGGACACAUGUCGCCUGCCAGUGCAGCCACACAGCCAGCUUUGCGGUGCUCAUGGAUAUCUCCAGGCGUGAGAACGGGGAGGUCCUGCCUCUGAAGAUUGUCACCUAUGCCGCUGUGUCCUUGUCACUGGCAGCCCUGCUGGUGGCCUUCGUCCUCCUGAGCCUGGUCCGCAUGCUGCGCUCCAACCUGCACAGCAUUCACAAGCACCUCGCCGUGGCGCUCUUCCUCUCUCAGCUGGUGUUCGUGAUUGGGAUCAACCAGACGGAAAACCCGUUUCUGUGCACAGUGGUUGCCAUCCUCCUCCACUACAUCUACAUGAGCACCUUUGCCUGGACCCUCGUGGAGAGCCUGCAUGUCUACCGCAUGCUGACCGAGGUGCGCAACAUCGACACGGGGCCCAUGCGGUUCUACUACGUCGUGGGCUGGGGCAUCCCGGCCAUUGUCACAGGACUGGCGGUCGGCCUGGACCCCCAGGGCUACGGGAACCCCGACUUCUGCUGGCUGUCGCUUCAAGACACCCUGAUUUGGAGCUUUGCGGGGCCCAUCGGAGCUGUUAUAAUCAUCAACACAGUCACUUCUGUCCUAUCUGCAAAGGUUUCCUGCCAAAGAAAGCACCAUUAUUAUGGGAAAAAAGGGAUCGUCUCCCUGCUGAGGACCGCAUUCCUCCUGCUGCUGCUCAUCAGCGCCACCUGGCUGCUGGGGCUGCUGGCUGUGAACCGCGAUGCACUGAGCUUUCACUACCUCUUCGCCAUCUUCAGCGGCUUACAGGGCCCCUUCGUCCUCCUUUUCCACUGCGUGCUCAACCAGGAGGUCCGGAAGCACCUGAAGGGCGUGCUCGGCGGGAGGAAGCUGCACCUGGAGGACUCCGCCACCACCAGGGCCACCCUGCUGACGCGCUCCCUCAACUGCAACACCACCUUCGGUGACGGGCCUGACAUGCUGCGCACAGACUUGGGCGAGUCCACCGCCUCGCUGGACAGCAUCGUCAGGGAUGAAGGGAUCCAGAAGCUCGGCGUGUCCUCUGGGCUGGUGAGGGGCAGCCACGGAGAGCCAGACGCGUCCCUCAUGCCCAGGAGCUGCAAGGAUCCCCCUGGCCACGAUUCCGACUCAGAUAGCGAGCUGUCCCUGGAUGAGCAGAGCAGCUCUUACGCCUCCUCACACUCGUCAGACAGCGAGGACGAUGGGGUGGGAGCUGAGGAAAAAUGGGACCCGGCCAGGGGCGCCGUCCACAGCACCCCCAAAGGGGACGCUGUGGCCAACCACGUUCCGGCCGGCUGGCCCGACCAGAGCCUGGCUGAGAGUGACAGUGAGGACCCCAGCGGCAAGCCCCGCCUGAAGGUGGAGACCAAGGUCAGCGUGGAGCUGCACCGCGAGGAGCAGGGCAGUCACCGUGGAGAGUACCCCCCGGACCAGGAGAGCGGGGGCGCAGCCAGGCUUGCUAGCAGCCAGCCCCCAGAGCAGAGGAAAGGCAUCUUGAAAAAUAAAGUCACCUACCCGCCGCCGCUGACGCUGACGGAGCAGACGCUGAAGGGCCGGCUCCGGGAGAAGCUGGCCGACUGUGAGCAGAGCCCCACAUCCUCGCGCACGUCUUCCCUGGGCUCUGGCGGCCCCGACUGCGCCAUCACAGUCAAGAGCCCUGGGAGGGAGCCGGGGCGUGACCACCUCAACGGGGUGGCCAUGAAUGUGCGCACUGGGAGCGCCCAGGCCGAUGGCUCCGACUCUGAGUGAGUAGCCUGGGCCUCCAGGGCGGGGAUCACCCACUUCCCCCUUGUCCUGAGUCAGGAGAGAGAGGGGGCAGUGGUCAGGGACCUGACACCCACCUCACCUGGAGCCCUGAGUGCAGAGGAAGCCCAGGCGGGGAUGGGGGAGGGGGGAGGCGCUGCAGCUGAGGUCAGGAGGAUACCCCGGAGAUGGGCAGACCCCCUAUCCUGGGGACACGUCUCAGGCCUCUGGGACUCUGAAGCCCUGGCCAGCCCCAAAAUGCUAGGACCUAAGGUGCUGGGCUCUGCGUUUGAUCAGCAUUGUCUCCGCCUGGGACCACUGCCACCCACCUUGCAGUUGAGGAUACUGAGGGUCCCGGAAUGCCAGGGGUGAAGGGGGCGGGGUGGAGCUGGGGUCCUGGCCCCAGACCUCUCCCUGUCGCCCCUCCCUCCCUCCAAACUCACAAGGGAGAAGCCAGGUCUUCAGAAUGCCCCUUCCAAAAGUCACUGUAGAGAUGGCCGGUUUCUAACGUGGAUUCCUUGCGCUCUUCUGAAAGACCAGCAACACAGAGGCCCACAGGCUGGUCCUGGUCCCCUCUCCUGCCUCCCAAGGGCAGCCUCAUCCAACAUGAGCUUGCCCUCCCUGGAGCCCCCAGACGCCCCCUCUACCCUGAUGGGGUGAUCCUGCCCCCCCGUGUGACAACCUUGGGCCCCACCAAGCCGCUACCCUCACUGACCCUUCACCUGCUUGCUGGCUUCUUCCCACGCGCAGAGGCAGUAAUGAAACUUCAAUUUGAACCAUCAGUAAUGAAACUUCAAUUUGAACCAUCAGGAAACCGUGAGGCAAGCCCGUCACCCCACACAGGCUGCGGCAUCACCCUCAGACCUUGGAGCCCAAGGGGCCACUGCCCUUGAAGUGGAGUGGGCCCAGAGUGUGGCGGUCCCCAUGGUGGCAGCCCCCCGACUGAUCAUCCAGACACAAAGGUCUUGGUUCUCCCAGGAGCUCAGGGCCUGUCAGACCUGGUGACAAGUGCCAAAGGCCACAGGCAUGAGGGAGGCGUGGACCACUGGGCCAGCACCGCUGAGUCCUAAGACUGCAGUCAAAGCCAGAACUGAGAGGGGACCCCAGACUGGGCCCAGAGGCUGGCCAGAGUUCAGGAACGCCGGGCACAGACCAAAGACCGCGGUCCAGCCCCGCCCAGGCGGGCAUCUCAUGGCAGUGCGGACCCGUGGCUGGCAGCCCGGGCAGUCCUUUGCAAAGGCACCCCUUGUCUUAAAAUCACUUCGCUAUGUGGGAAAGGUGGAGAUACUUUUAUAUAUUUGUAUGGGACUCUGAGGAGGUGCAACCUGUAUAUAUAUUGCAUUCGUGCUGACUUUGUUAUCCCGAGAGAUCCAUGCAAUGAUCUCUUGCUGUCUUCUCUGUCAAGAUUGCACAGUUGUACUUGAAUCUGGCAUGUGUUGACGAAACUGGUGCCCCAGCAGAUCAAAGGUGGGAAAUACGUCAGCAGUGGGGCUAAAACCAAGCGGCUAGAAGCCCUACAGCUGCCUUCGGCCAGGAAGUGAGGAUGGUGUGGGCCCUCCCCGCCGGCCCCCUGGGUCCCCAGUGUUCGCUGUGUGUGCGUUUGUCCUCUGCUGCCAUCUGCCCCGGCUGUGUGAAUUCAAGACAGGGCAGUGCAGCACUAGGCAGGUGUGAGGAGCCCUGCUGAGGUCACUGUGGGGCACGGUUGCCACACGGCUGUCAUUUUUCACCUGGUCAUUCUGUGACCACCACCCCCUCCCCUCACCGCCUCCCAGGUGGCCCGGGAGCUGCAGGUGGGGAUGGCUUUGUCCUUUGCUCCUGCUCCCCGUGGGACCUGGGACCUUAAAGCGUUGCAGGUUCCUGAUUUGGACAGAGGUGUGGGGCCUUCCAGGCCGUUACAUACCUCCUGCCAAUUCUCUAACUCUCUGAGACUGCGAGGAUCUCCAGGCAGGGUUCUCCCCUCUGGAGUCUGACCAAUUACUUCAUUUUGCUUCAAAUGGCCAAUUGUGCAGAGGGACAAAGCCACAGCCACACUCUUCAACGGUUACCAAACUGUUUUUGGAAAUUCACACCAAGGUCGGGCCCACUGCAGGCAGCUGGCACAGCGUGGCCCGAGGGGCUGUGGAACGGGUCCCGGAACUGUCAGACAUGUUUGAUUUUAGCGUUUCCUUUGUUCUUCAAAUCAGGUGCCCAAAUAAGUGAUCAGCACAGCUGCUUCCAAAUAGGAGAAACCAUAAAAUAGGAUGAAAAUCAAGUAAAAUGCAAAGAUGUCCACACUGUUUUAAACUUGACCCUGAUGAAAAUGUGAGCACUGUUAGCAGAUGCCUAUGGGAGAGGAAAAGCGUAUCUGAAAAUGGUCCAGGACAGGAGGAUGAAAUGAGAUCCCAGAGUCCUCACACCUGAAUGAAUUAUACAUGUGCCUUACCAGGUGAGUGGUCUUUCGAAGAUAAAAAACUCUAGUCCCUUUAAACGUUUGCCCCUGGCGUUUCCUAAGUACGAAAAGGUUUUUAAGUCUUCGAACAGUCUCCUUUCAUGACUUUAACAGGAUUCUGCCCCCUGAGGUGUAAUUUUUUUGUUCUAUUUUUUUCCACGUACUCCACAGCCAACAUCACGAGGUGUAAUUUUUAAUUUGAUCAGAACUGUUACCAAAAAACAACUGUCAGUUUUAUUGAGAUGGGAAAAAUGUAAACCUAUUUUUAUUACUUAAGACUUUAUGGGAGAGAUUAGACACUGGAGGUUUUUAACAGAACGUGUAUUUAUUAAUGUUCAAAACACUGGAAUUACAAAUGAGAAGAGUCUACAAUAAAUUAAGAUUUUUGAAUUUGUA